CUCUGCCCGCCUCGCCCUCGCCCGGGCCUCCUCCCGCUUUCUCUCUCCGCUUCCCCUGGAGCCUCCGAGGAGUCCGCAGCCGCUGGGCGCCCGGGAAGAUGGCGGCGGCGGCGGGAGACGGCGGCGGCGAGGGGGGCGCGGGCCUGGGCAGCGCGGCGGGGCUGGGGCCGGGGCCGGGGCUGCGCGGGCAGGGCCCCUCAGCCGAAGCGCACGAGGGCGCCCCGGACCCGAUGCCCGCCGCGCUGCACCCUGAGGAGGUCGCCGCGCGACUGCAGCGGAUGCAGCGGGAGCUGAGCAACCGCAGGAAAAUCCUGGUGAAAAACCUGCCCCAGGACAGCAACUGCCAGGAAGUUCAUGAUUUGUUAAAAGACUAUGACUUAAAAUAUUGUUAUGUGGACAGAAAUAAACGAACAGCUUUUGUUACCUUAUUGAAUGGGGAACAAGCCCAGAACGCAAUUCAGAUGUUUCAUCAAUAUUCUUUUAGAGGAAAAGACUUAAUAGUCCAGCUUCAGCCAACAGAUGCUUUGUUGUGUAUUACCAACGUGCCCAUUUCUUUUACAUCAGAAGAGUUUGAAGAACUUGUUCGUGCUUAUGGAAAUAUUGAGAGAUGUUUUCUGGUCUAUAGUGAAGUUACUGGCCAUUCCAAAGGCUAUGGAUUUGUGGAAUACAUGAAAAAGGACUUUGCUGCAAAGGCUAGACUGGAGCUAUUGGGUAGACAGUUGGGAGCAUCAGCACUCUUUGCACAAUGGAUGGAUGUUAAUCUAUUGGCUUCAGAGCUCAUUCAUUCUAAGUGCCUUUGUAUUGAUAAACUCCCCAGUGACUACAGGGAUUCAGAAGAGCUGUUGCAAAUUUUUUCCAGUGUCCAUAAACCUGUGUUUUGCCAGCUUGCACAGGAUGAAGGUAGUUACGUUGGUGGCUUUGCAGUGGUUGAAUAUAGCACUGCGGAGCAGGCUGAAGAGGUCCAGCAGGCAGCAGACGGUAUGACCAUCAAGGGCAGCAAAGUCCAGGUUUCCUUCUGUGCUCCUGGAGCGCCAGGGCGAAGUACAUUAGCAGCAUUGAUAGCGGCUCAACGUGUGAUGCACAGUAAUCAAAAGGGCUUACUUCCAGAGCCAAAUCCAGUACAAAUUAUGAAAAGUUUAAACAACCCUGCCAUGUUGCAAGUUCUUCUACAGCCCCAGUUAUGUGGACGAGCUGUUAAACCAGCCGUUCUUGGAACACCUCACAGCUUGCCACAUCUGAUGAAUCCAUCCAUCUCUCCUGCAUUUUUACAUUUGAAUAAAGCACAUCAGAGCUCAGUUAUGGGUAAUACUUCUAAUUUAUUCCUUCAGAAUCUUUCUCAUAUACCACUGGCACAACAACAAUUAAUGAAGUUUGAGAAUAUUCAUACUAAUAAUAAACCCGGCUUACUUGGAGAGCCCCCAGCUGUGGUACUUCAGACUGCACUAGGGAUAGGGUCAGUGCUUCCAUUGAAAAAGGAGUUGGGACAUCAUCAUGGAGAAGCACAUAAAACAUCUAGCCUGAUUCCAACUCAAACAACGAUAACAGCUGGAAUGGGCAUGUUACCAUUCUUUCCAAAUCAGCACAUUGCUGGACAGGCUGGGCCAGGGCACAGUAAUACUCAGGAGAAACAGCCAGCCACGGUGGGAAUGGCAGAAGGAAAUUUCUCAGGGUCGCAGCCUUAUCUUCAGAGCUUUCCAAACCUUGCUGCUGGAAGCUUGCUGGUGGGACACCAUAAGCAGCAGCAAAGCCAGCCAAAAGGCACAGAGAUAAGUUCAGGGGCUGCCUCUAAGAAUCAAACUUCACUCUUGGGAGAACCACCAAAAGAAAUUCGGCUCAGUAAAAAUCCAUACUUGAAUUUGGCAAGUGUGUUGCCCAGUGUGUGCUUAUCAUCCCCUGCAAGUAAAACCACUCUUCAUAAGACUGGAAUUGCAAGCAGCAUUCUGGAUGCAAUCUCUCAGGGAAGUGAAUCACAACACGCAUUGGAAAAGUGCAUUGCUUAUUCUCCACCUUUUGGUGAUUAUGCACAGGUGUCAUCUUUAAGAAAUGAAAAGCGAGGCUCAUCAUAUCUCAUCUCUGCCCCAGAAGGUGGUUCAGUGGAAUGUGUUGACCAGCAUUCUCAGGGCACAGGAGCAUAUUACAUGGAAACUUACUUAAAAAAGAAGCGAGUAUACUGAGUUAAGCUCUCUCCUAAUAACCCCCUAAGGUUCUCUGCAGUAUCUCUGCUGUUCAUCGCUGCCUUAACUUCAUUCAAACUAGCCAUAUCCUUUAAAUACGGGUUUAUAGUUUCCCAGAAGGAACUGUGUUGUGCAGCAGGCAGAAAUGCCAAAUAAAAAAUAGCAAUAAGAAGAGACAUCAAUUGAGGACAUUUUCCACUAGAGUCAGAUGCAUCUUAAUCAGUGUGCUAACUUACAAUCCAUUGGAGAAACUAACAAUGUUCCAAUAUUCCUUGAUUUAGGACUGGGAAUAAUUCUGACACCAUAUAUAAAAGAAGUUUGAAGCAAUAAAUGGGAAACAGUGUUGUUUCCUGAGCCUUAGAAGAAUGAGUUUCUUAUAAGCCAAUGUGCAUUUCAAUUUACUUUCCCUAGAAGUAAUUGCAUUUAUAGAUUUUUAGGACUUUUCCUAGAACUACAAGGGUGCAAGUACCAAAUGUGCUGAUGGUAAUAUUAUAAAGAUGCUCUACAUGCACACUCAAUUACGCCCACACCAGCCAUGCAAAAUUAAACCCGGUAAGAGAGUGACAGUGAUAUCCAAGGUAUCCACUACUACCGAUGCUUUAAGAUGUUGUUUACCAUUUAUACCUUCUGUGAAAAAUAGAAGGUAUUUUAAGAAAAGUAACUUUGGUGAUCUAAUAAAAGGGUUUGGCAAACUACACCCUGGGUCCACAUUUGGUCUACCACCCGCUUUUGUGCUGCCUGCAAGCUAAGACUAAUGUUUACAUUUUUAAAUGGUUGGAGGAAAAAAGAAAACUUAUGACAUGAAAUUUAUAUGAAAUUCAGAUUUCAGUGUCCAUAAAUAAACUUUUAUUGGGACGUUGCCAUGCUCAUUCAUUUACGUGUUGUCUGUGGCACUCUUACGCUACAAGGGCAGAACUGAUUAGCUUCAACAGAGACUGUAUGGCCUACAAAGACCAUAUGGCCUAAAAUUUCAAGUAUCUGGCCAUUUAUAUAUAGUUUGCUGAUCCCUGAUCUAAUAGCACUAAUUCUAAUAGCAACUAUUCCUUUCAAUUCACCUAAAGACAGACCUUUAGCCUUUAGACAGACUUGUAAGUGGAAAGGAACAUGGGUUUCUGUGCUCAUUUCAUAGCGUAGACUAGUAAUGAUCUAAUGACUAGAAUGGGGCCUAUUUUGAUCACUAAAUGCCCUAUUAUUUCCACAAUAUAGUAUAGUAAAGCAGUCAAUACUGCACUUUCUGAUGGAGUCUUAAGGAGUCACAGUAUUUAUAACCAUUUUGAGCUAAUAAGCUAUACCUCACUCUCUGCUUUCUCUCUCACUCUUUUUGAUAGUGUGUUAGGGUGAAAAAUCAGUUAUUUAACCCAAUUUACUUGUGAAAGAAGUUUUAUCUUUAUGGACUAUGAUGACUUUUGACAUCACCAUUUCUUGAAGACCUUGGUAUUAAAUGCAUGAGAAACCUUUUGCCAUCUAGAAAUUUCUAAGUUUGUUUAUGUUAUAAGACUGUAAUUAAUUGAUAGGGAAUUUGGGAUCUCAAUCCGGGGCUUUUUGAAAUCAGAUCAUUAAAUAUCUCGUCACUUUGGGGACUUGUUAUUUUUAACUAUGAUGUGGAUAUCCUGUUUUAAUUAUGAAGUCUAGAAUUGGUACAUAUGUUGUAUGCUUUGUAAAGAAUUUCACUUGGUCUAAUUUAUUGCAUAUACUAGCUUCUGUUGGAAAAUGACUGACAGCUAGAAAGUUUAAGGUAAUUUCUAAGUAUACUACCUAUAAGUAACUGAUAAGAAUUAGGCAUCAUUCAGUGAUAUAGCAGAUGACUAAUGGGUUUUUCAGGCCCUGCACUUCUCUUUCCCAUUUUCCUGUUGCAUUCAGCCUCUUCAAUGCUUAGUCACACCUCCACUAUAGUACAAACAAACAAACAAACAGAAGAAAGGAAAGAUGGUGAAUUUUGCAACAGAGCUGCAAAAAGUCAGUCAGUCAAAGCAGGAAGAGGUUGAAGGAACUAAAACAAACAAACAAAGGUGUCUGGACUACAGCACAGUGGACAUGCCAUCCAUACUGGCCUGUGCCCCGUUAUCAAUCACUGGGCACAACAGUGAAGAAGUGCAAAUCAAGUGGUGUUUGUUUGUUUGUUAGUAGUAAGGACCGUAACCCACCCCUUCCUCCCCCCAAAACUAUACUGUUAUUUUUCUAUGUAAGCAAAUUGUUUGAAAUGCUUUGAAAAUGAAAUCUUAAUAUUAAAAGGCAUAUGCAUGUAAA